AGACGCUCUCCCCGCCCAAAGAGGGAAGGCGGGCGGGACUCCCCAACCGGCUUGCCCCGGUCCCCCUGGGCCCCAUGAAUAACCAGGCGCGGACCCCAGCCCCCUCCUCGGCGCGGACUUCAACCUCAGUCCGGGCUUCUACCCCGACCCGGACACCGACUCCACUCCGGACCCCGACUCCGGUCCGGACUCGGACCCCCAUCCGGACCCUGACUCCAGUCCUGACUCCGUCUCCAGCCGGGACUUCCCCUCUGGUCCUGACUCCUGCUCCAGCCCAGAUUCCCACUCUGGUCCCCACUCCCGCUCUGGCCCGGAUCCCCCGUCUGGUUCCGCCUCCUGCUCCGGCCUGGAUCCCUACUCCGGUGCCGACUCCCGUUCCCGUCCGGAACCCAACUCCGGUCCCGACUCCGGCUCGGACCCUGACUCCUCCAGUCCGGGUCCCAGCCCCAGCCCCAGCCCAGCUCCUGGCAGGGAUUCGGGCCGCGCUCCCCGUCUUGGACUCCUACCUGGCCCCGGCCCUACCUUUGGAUCCGCCCCCGGAACCUGCUCCGGAGCUGCCUUUGUUGCCCGAGGAGGACCCUGAGCCGGCGCCGAGCCUGAAGCUCAUCCCGUCGGUCUCCAGCGAGGCCGGGCCCGCCCCGGGGCCCCUUCCCACGCGCACCCCGCUGGCCGCGAACUCACCCGGGCCCACCCUGGACUUCACCUUCAGGGCAGACCCGUCGGCCAUCGGGCUGGCGGAUCCCCCCAUUCCCAGUCCUGUCCCCUCGCCCAUCCUGGGGACCAUCCCGUCGGCCAUCUCCUUACAGAAUUGUACGGAAACCUUCCCCUCCUCCAGCGAGAACUUCGCGCUGGACAAGAGGGUCCUGAUUCGAGUGACCUACUGUGGCCUCUGAAGCUAUAGCCUUCGGUACAUUCUACUGAAAAAGAGCCUGGAGCAGCAAUUUCCGAAUCACCUACUCUUUGAGGAGGACAGAGCUGCCCAGGCUACAGGGGAGUUUGAGGUGUUUGUGAACGGGAGACUGGUCCAUUCCAAGAAGAGGGGUGAUGGCUUUGUGAACGAGUCCAGGCUGCAGAAAAUUGUGAGCGUUAUCGAUGAGGAAAUCAAGAAAAGGUAGCCGGCAAGGGGUGGAGCUGGAGGAGUCUCAGCUGGAUGAUGAGAAGGGCUGAAAUGUUGCCAAGUCAGGUCCUUUUCUGAUGGUGGCUGGGGCUGGGGUGAGCUCAGGGAGGGGAAGAGGAGAAUACAUGCAGAGUCAGCACCCCUGUGUCCAGUCUGACUGUGUCUGCUGUCGCCACACUCACCUCUGAGGUCUGUGGAAGUCACCUGAUAUUCUGGCCCCAGGGGUGGGAGGGAGGGGAGCUUGGAAGGCUAGUCCUGUAGCUCCAGUCCUCUGUCUGGCCUCCACUCCUCUUGCUCCUGAGGGCAGUUUGUUUCUUUUGUGGAUUCGUCAUUUCCCAUGCCCUGGUUCCAGAUACAUUUUGAAAACCUUCCAUCUUAUUGGCAUUUUCUGGGGUUGUGAGGGAAACGGGGAUGGCAGUCAGACUCAAACCCGUGACACUCCAAACUCGAUUAUGCUCCAGGGCCCACUUUCUAAACCUGUAAGAUCUAUGUUCCAGCCUGCGCAACAUAGUGAGACCCCAACUCUACAAAAAAUAAAAAAUUAGCCAGG